CAAGAAAAAUAAUAUUGCAUUUCCCUAUGUCAAAGGAACACUUUUAAUGGUAACUUGUCAGACUAUGAACAAACCCACUUUUUAAGAUAUUGAUAAAGUCUUCUUUUCUUCACGUGAUAUUUUAUACAAGAACACUUCAGAUGUAUUGGAUGUGGCUGAUUUUAACAAAUCCUAUUAGAUUUGUAUCAAUUAGUUACAUGUUCUAUUCAUAGUCUUUUGUGAAUCAUUGCCUUUUUGUUUAAAAAGAUGGCCUAUUUUGAGCCUUUGUAUAAGUACAUUCCUGUUUUUGUGACAAAAGAAAAACUUUAAAUUUGUCCCAAAGAGAAAAAUAAUGGCUAUCAGAAGUAUGCUUUGUUUUAGUGCGAGUUACCGUUACUGUAUUUGUGUAUUGUAAAAGUGGACAUUCUAAUUACAUUAAAAUGUAAUUAGAAAAAAGUGCUUAAUGAACAAAAACAGAACAUAGACAACAAAAGAAUAUUAGAAGUGAUGCAUGAAGAAAACGAGAUAUCAAUAAAAAGAUUUUUAAAAACCAAGAAAAAUUGUGACUCUGAAGAACACAGUAACUAUAUUAAAAAUUUAAUCAGCAGUCACAAAAGCGGAUUUAAUAAAGCAGAAAAAAUUAGACAGUUGAUAACAUUGCACUUAUAAAUACUGAUUCAUGAAAACAAAUUUUUUAAACAGAAUAGAGAAAAAAUCAAAAUUGGGACUUACAGCACACCACCAAGUGGACCACUGUAUUUAUAAAAGGAGUCUUAGAAAAACAGUAUAGGAGAAAAAUAAUAAAGAGGAUAUUUUUAAAAAGUAGCUGAGAACUCCCUAGAUGACAAGGUAAUUAAACAAGAAGAAAUCAUGCUAAACAAAAACCUUCAACUGGAAUAAUUUCACUUCAGAAAAAAAAGUUAAGCAUUUCCAAAACAAAUAAAAGUUGAGUGUGUUACUAGCCACUGGAACAGUGCUAAAGGAAAUGUAAAAGAAAGUCUAUCACGUCCAAAAAUGACAAUAUAUGCUGCACAGCGUCAUAAAAGCAUAUGAAAAUAGAAAGCUCUCUAUUAAAGGUAAAUACAUAAACAGCUAUAGAAACCUCUACUGUCAUAAUGAUGGUGCACAAAACUUUCACGUUAUUGCUAUGGAAUUUAAAAAAUGAAGCAGAAAGCUGCAUAAAUAUGGGUUCAUAGAUACUCAAUAAGAAAAGAUAACAAGUGAUAUUAAUAACAAAGUGGGGGUAUAAAGAGGUAAAGCUUUGCAUUCCAUUGAAAUAUAGUCAUUAUAUAUUGUCAUAACUUUAAGAUGUUUUAUGAAGUCUUUAUUUCUCAAGAUGAUUACAAAAAAACCUGUAGAUGGUAUGCAGAAGCAAAUGAGAAAGAAAUUGAAUCAUGUCACUACAAAAUCAAUGAAGAAAAAUAAAGCAGUAAGAGAAAAAAAUGAUAAAUAACACAUCUACAAGAAACACAGAAGACAAUUACAAAUAAUAAUAGUAACUUCAUUAACUACAGUAAUUACUUCAAAUACAAAAAGUUAAAUACCUUAAAGAAAAUGCAUAAAAUGAUUUAAUGGAUUAAGAACAAAGAAGAUCCAGCAAUGUACUCUCUACAAGAGUCACUUUAGCUCUAAGGACCCAAAUAAGUUGAAAGUAGCAGUAUAAAGAAAAUAUAUUUUAUGCAAAGAGUAGCUACAAUUGGAGGGGCAUGGUCAUAAUUAUAUUAAACAAAAUAUAUUUUAAGUUAAAAAUUUUAAAAAGAGACAGAUUGUUAUUAUGUAACGGUGAGAUGGAUUAACUUGCAAGAAAUCCAUAACAAUAAUUUAGAAAUCAUAUAUAUAAUUUGAAAAAUUAUACCAUCUGCAAAAUCUGCAAAAAUAUACCAUUGGGAUUUUGAUAAAAAUUACAUUAAAUUUUUAUAUUACUAUAAAUAACACUGAUAUCUUUCUUAUUUUUUUUUUUGGAGUUAGAGUUUCUGUCUCCCAGGCUGGAGGACAAUGGCACGAUCUCGCGAUUGGCUCACUUCAACCUCCGCCUCCCAGGUUCAACUGAUUCUCGUCUUUCAAAUAUGUAAAACAAAUAUUGACAGAAGUCAAGCAAGAAAUAUAUAGCAACACAACAAUUGCGGACUUCAAGACUCCGCUUUCAAUAAUGACUAGAAUAGUCAGAUGUAAUAUCAGUAAGAAAGCCAAACCUGAACAUUAUAGACCUAACAAGCAUUUACAGAACUCUGUGAUCGAAAGCAGCAAAAUAUGCAAUAUUCUCAAUCACACAUGGUACAUUCUGUUAGGAUACAUGUCUUAUUAAAUUUAAGAAAACUGAAGUCAUGCAAUGUAAAUGAAACUAGAAAUCAAAAGCAAGAAAAUGUUUCAGAUACGUAAAUAAGAGGAAAUUAAGCAAAAUCUUACAUAUAGUCUUGCUCAAGUGUCAGGUGAUUUAAUAUUGUUAAGAUGUCAGGGCCGGCGCGUGACUCAUGCCUGUAAUCCCAGGACUUUGGGAGGCCAAAGUGUGUGGAUCACUUGAGAUCAGAAGUUUGAGACUAGCCUGGCCAACAUGGCAAAACCCUAUCUCUACUAAAAAUACAAAAGUUAGCUAUACAUGUUGGUGCAUGACUGUAAUCCCAGCUACUCUGGUGGCUGAGACUGGAGAACUGGUGGCUGAGACUGGAGAAUUGCUUGAACAUGGGAAGCAGAGCUUGCAGUGAGCACAGCUCACACCACUGCCCUUCAGCCUGAGUGACUCACUAAAACUCCAUCUCCAAAGGAAAAAAAAAAGGUUGUCAGUAUUACCCAUGAUGAUAUAAAAAUGUAAUGUAAUUUUCAUCUAAAUCCCAAUGGUAUUUUUUUUGCAGAAUUUUUGUGUAUAAUUCUAAAAGUUGUUUAGGAAGUGUGACUAGGCAAACACCCUUUAAAAAGGACAAAGAGUUAUUACAUUUUCUGAUUUAAAAUCAUGAUACAAAGCUACAAAAAUAAAAACAAUAUGGUAUUGCCACAAAAACGGAUACAUAGAUGAUGAAACAGAAUAGACAUCCUGGAAAUAAACCCUCGCAUACGUGAUAAAAUAAUCUUCCAUAUGCUUUCCAUGACCAUGCAAUAGAAAAAUAAGAAUCUCUUUAACAAAGGAUUUUCAAAAUUGAAUGUUUACAGAGCAAAAAUAAAGUUGGAUGCUUCUUUUGUAUUAUACAUAAAAACAAAAGUUGAUUUUUAAUGGAUUUAAUGCUUAAACAUAAAAACUAAUAAAAUUCUUAGAAGUAAACAUAGGGGAAAAGUUUAUGACAUAAGUCUUAAAACUUUGCUUAAGUAUGACAUCAAAUUCAUAAGAAACAAGGAAAAGAACAAAAAAGAAAGGAACUACAUUAACCUUCAAGUAUUCUACACAUCAAGGAAAACAUUUAGUGGCAUACAAAUGUCUCCUAAUAAGUGGGUGAAACCUGGGUAUGCUGGCUCAAGCCUAUAAUUCUAGAAAUUUAGGAGGCCAAGUCAGAACGAUCAUUUGAGGCCAAAAGUUUGAGACUAGCCAUGAAAAUAUAUCAAGACCCUGUCUUGUAUAGGGUAAUAUAUGUGCAUACAUACAUACAUAUAACAAAAAAGUGUAAAAAUAUUUUCUAAUCACAUAUUUGGUAGGUGUUAAUUUCCAAAAGAUAUAAACUUCUGAAAUUCAACAACAACAAAAAGUUAAUAACUUGAUUUAGAAUGGUAAAUGUUUGAAAUGACCUUUCUCCAAAGAAGACAUAGAAAUGACUAGGUAUUUAAAAGGAUACUCGUCCGAGGGCAGGACUAUGGGAGGCUGCCCUGUACGGAAAAGAAGAAGAAAUGGCAGUAAAGAGGGCAACCAUCAUUCCACCCAGCCCAAAAGGAAUAAGAGAAACCCUAUCUUUCAGGAUUCUCAAGACACAGUUUUCAUGGAGUGAUAAUGAAAGGAGCAGCAGCCGCCUUAAUAUCCCAGAGAGAGAAGAUGGACGAGAAGGCAACUUAAACCAGAUUGUUACUGAACCCAAUGCAAACUUUCCCUAGUUCUUGCAUGAGGGGUAUGUAUCAUGCCAAGGUCUUUACUCCCAUAUCAACCAGAUCUUGAAGGAGGCUCACUUCAACAGCCUGCAGCAGUGAGGGCAAGCUCCAACAUGAUGAAUUAGGACUUCCUUAUUCCAACCUAAACUGUGUUUAUAAAAGUAAUUGCAUACACACCAAAAAAAAAGUCUAUUGGUUUUUAAGUCUAAAUUUUAAGUAACAAGUUAAUGGGCAGUUGUUUAAUUGGGGUUUUACUUCACUGCUGUACUUUUAAAGAGGCUGUGAAUAAAUGUUUAUGAAAUUUAAAAAAUAAAAUAAAAAAAUAAAAGGAUACUCGACAUCACUCUUCUAGAAAAAUGCAAAGCAAAGUCACAAUAAUCUACGGCCUCAAGCCGAUAUUUAAAAUAGUAUGACAGCUCUUCAAAAAAUUUAAAAUGAGAUUAUUAUAUAAUCCAGCAAACCCCCUUCUGGCUAUGUACUUAAAAUAUACAACGCAGAUCUGGAAGAGAUAUUUGCACAACCAAAUUUAUUGCAAUAUUAUUAACACAAGCCAAAAGGCAGAAACAAUCCAGAUGUCCCUUGACCAAUGAACAGAUUAAUAACAAGUGGCACAUAAACAAAGUCGAAUAUUAUUCAGUCUUUAAAAAGACACAUUAUAUGAUAAUUCUGGAGAAGAUCAUGUUAAUUGAAAUAAGCCAGGAACAAAGUGACAGUCUAUGAUUCCAUUCAUAAUCAGGUAUCUUAAGUAGAUAUACUCAUAGGAAAAAAAAGUUAGAAUGGUGCUUGUCAAGGACUGAAGAGAUGGUAAAAUGAGCAGUUGUUUUAUUUUUUAUUUUUUUAUUUUUUUAAAUUAUACUUUAAGUUUUA